ACAGAACCCGUUGAGCUUCGUGCCCGGCAGCACCCCCGGUCCCCCGCGCGGGGCGGACUUGCGGCGGGACAGGUGUAGCCCGCAGCCGCAGGCGCUGCGCUCAGGACUGGGCGGGCUCGGCUGGCCGGUCCCCGCCACGCAGGCCGGUCCCCGCCACGCAGGCCGGUCGGUGAGCCACUUCGCACCGCCACAGCCCUAGCAUCGGGCCACCAGCCGGGGUGAAGAAAGUCACGGCGGAGCCCGGCUCCCCAGUCCUGAUGCUGGCUGCCGGUGGCGGGCUCCACGCCGGCCCCGGGACCUAGGCAGCCGCGCGAGACCGCUGCGGGCGCCUCCCCCAUGCUGCUCGGAGCGUCCUGGCUGUGCGCAUCCAAGGCGGCCGCCGCUGCUGCGCAGAGCGAGGGCGACGAGGACAGGCCAGGCGAGCGACGGCGGCGUCGGGCGGCGGCCACCGCCGCGGGGGCGGGCGAGGACAUGGACGAGUCGUCGCUGCUGGACCUGCUGGAGUGCUCCGUGUGUCUGGAGCGCCUGGACACCACGGCCAAGGUGCUGCCAUGCCAACACACUUUCUGCCGCCGCUGCCUGGAGAGCAUCGUGUGCUCGCGCCACGAGCUGCGCUGCCCCGAGUGCCGCAUCCUGGUGGGCUGCGGCGUGGACGAACUGCCCGCCAACAUCUUGCUGGUGCGACUGCUGGACGGCAUCCGUCAGCGGCCCCGCGCGGGCACCAGCCCCGGCGGCAGCCCGCCCGCGCGUCCCAUCCCAGGCCAGAGUGCGGCCCCCACGCUCGCGGGCGGCGGGGGCGGCGCGGCAGGCAGCACCCCGGGUUCCCCGGUUUUCCUCUCCGCGGCCGCGGGCAGCACCGCCGGCAGUCUGCGGGAGCUGGCGACCAGCAGGACCGCGCCGGCGGCAAAGAAUCCCUGCCUGCUUCCCUAUGGCAAGGCCCUCUACAGCUACGAGGGGAAGGAACCUGGUGACCUCAAGUUCAACAAGGGGGACAUCAUCGUCCUGCGGCGCAAGGUGGAUGAACAGUGGUACCACGGCGAGCUGCACGGCACACAGGGCUUCCUCCCAGCCAGCUAUAUCCAGUGCAUCCAGCCCUUGCCACACGCCCCGCCCCAGGGAAAAGCACUUUAUGAUUUCGAGAUGAAGGACAAAGACCAAGACAAGGACUGUCUGACCUUCACCAAGGACGAGAUUCUGACGGUGCUCAGGAGAGUGGAUGAGAACUGGGCGGAAGGCAUGCUGGGAGACAAGAUCGGGAUCUUCCCGCUCCUGUACGUGGAGCUCAAUGACUCCGCCAAGCAGCUCAUUGAGAUGGACAAGCCAUGCCCAGCCGCUGCAUCCAGCUGCAAUGCCUCCCUGCCCUCUGACUCCGGCGCUGUGGCCAGCGUGGCCCCAAGUCCCACUUUAAGCAGCUCAGGGGCGGUCAGUGCCUUUCAGCGGCGUGUGGAUGGCAAGAAGAACACCAAGAAACGCCACUCCUUCACCGCGCUCAGUGUGACGCACAGAUCCUCCCAGGCUGCCAGCCACAGGCAUUCCAUGGAAAUUAGUGCUCCAGUGUUGAUCAGCUCCAGCGAUCCCCGAGCCGCGGCCAGGAUUGGAGACCUUGCUCAUCUGUCGUGCGCUGCUCCCACCCAGGAUGUCUCCUCCUCGGCGGGAUCUACCCCCACGGCUGUCCCACGGGCUGCCUCGGUGUCUGGAGAGCAGGGCACGCCUCCCAAGGUCCAGCUGCCCCUCAACGUGUACCUGGCGCUCUACGCCUACAAGCCCCAGAAGAGUGACGAGCUGGAGCUGCACAAGGGAGAGAUGUACCGGGUCCUCGAGAAGUGUCAGGAUGGCUGGUUCAAGGGGGCGUCUCUGAGGACCGGGGUCUCUGGGGUGUUCCCCGGAAACUACGUGACACCCGUUUCCAGGGUGCCUGCAGGAGGGGCAGGGCCGCCCCGGAAUAAUGUAGUCGGAGGGUCUCCACUGGCCAAAGGGAUAACCACAACCAUGCACCCAGGCAGUGGGAGUCUGAGCAGCCUGGCCACUGCCACCAGGCCCGCCCUGCCCAUCACCACUCCCCAGGCCCACGCCCAGCACCCCACAGCCUCGCCCCCAACAGGCAGCUGUCUACGGCACUCAGCCCAGCCAACGGCCAGCCAAGCCCGGAGCACCAUUUCAACAGCUGCCCACUCUGCAGCCCAGGCUCAGGACCGGCCAACUGCCACCGUGUCACCCCUGCGCACCCAGAACUCUCCAUCCCGCCUGCCUGCCACCAGCCUCAGGCCCCACUCGGUGGUGUCCCCGCAGCACAGCCACCAGCCCCCGGUGCAGAUGUGCCCACGGCCGGCCAUCCCCCUCACAUCAGCAGCAUCAGCCAUCACACCUCCCAACGUCAGUGCCGCAAACCUCAACGGGGAGGCUGGAGGGGGGCCCAUCGGUGUUCUGUCCACAUCCAGCCCCACCAACACGGGAUGCAAACUAGACGAGAAGAAAAGUGAAAAGACCCCCAAAACCAUCCACAGACCACUGAUGAAGACCCCGGGACUCACUGCCCUCAGAGCCUUCAUACGGCAGCACCUAACCCACCUGCAGCACGAGGAUCUCCCUGGAGCUCUUGCUCCAGCCCAGCCCGGUUUUGCUGACAGCCCCUCUGCAGCCCAGUGGUAUGCAGGUGACAUGUCCCCUGAGGCCACGCGUCAUCACAGCCUGAGGGAAGCAGUGGUUUCAACCCUGCUGUGGGUUGAGGACAAUUGUCUAGAGGAAAGGACCCCAUCCUGGCACUUCUCCUUUAGCUGAGAGGUGAUACUUUCUUUUCCAACAUAGUGAGAAAGCAACACUUGCAUAUCAACCACAUUAAGACAUCUGCUUUCAGAAAAGAAGGCGUUGUGCCCAACAUCUGCAUGGCACCAAACAUCUGUACUGUAGCCUUGUUGAUGACCAGAGCAGGCAAGGCGGCAUCUCCCAGGUGCCCAGCACUUGAGCCCCAUGUUUGAUCCCCACAGCCACCCUCUAUGACAGGUGCUGUCGCUAUCCCCAGUUUACAGAUGGGAGAACUGAACAGAAGACAUAAGGCAUUUGUUCAAGGGUGCAUGGCUGGUGAGUAGUGAAGCCAGCUAAGAUGGCCAUGAGGCUGAGAAAAAGAGAGUAAUAAGGAGAGGAGUCCAGAUGCCAGCCCCUGUUAGUCCUGAGGGUGCCAAGGUCAUAGGGAGGUGACAUCAGACUGGCUGAAUUAGUGUCUCAGGGGGCAGCCAACACUUGUCACUCAGGAAGUCUCGCAGGGUAGAGGUCAUCCCGAGCAGCCAUGGGGUGCUCUCUGCUGCCCUGUGGGAGGAGGAGGAGGAGGAUGGAGACGAACAAUGCUGUACUGGCAUGUGGAGGGGUGGAGCACACUGGGUACAGGCUCCUAACCUCUGUCUUGGCCUCAUUCCCCUCCUCUCCUCCUGGAUCCCCUGGGCUCACCUGGCUGCUUGCCUGGGCACAGGGACCUGGGACAUUAUGACCUCCGGCUCUCUCUAGCUGGGACCUCAUGGAGGGCGGUUCGCUGUUCUCUAGCUUGGAGCUUGGGGCAUCUGUGGAUGGUUUGAUUUGUGUGGUUUCUGUCUUAAAAGAAUGUCUAGAAGAAGCGGCAGAUAAAAGGCCUGGAGCUCACUGGAGAGUUGGGUUUGAGAUACUUCAGCCAUGGAAGGGAGAACUGAAGAGCCAAGCUGUGUCAUUGCUUCAGGCAAGAGGACACCGAUAGGGAAACAGAGGGACAGGCAGCCUGAGGGCAUUUCUCACCUGCUGCUGCCAAAAAGAAUCUGACAGCUGUUCAGAAAGGCAGGAGAAGAAACCCUAAGACGUGUCAAGAAAUCCAUGAGAGGGGAACAUCUCAAUGGAGAGGUGAGGGGGAGGCCGGGGCCCUGCAGACGUCAGGUUGGGUGGCGAGGGUCCCCCCACACAGGUCUCUCUGUGCUCAAGCUCCAGUCACCAUGCUGUCACCACAGUUGCUGUGUCUGCUGGCAGCUGGAGGGUGCACCUGUGCCUUCCACUCAGCAAACUGAGUUUGAGCAAAUACGGAAAAACAAGUUUAUUGCGGCUAUGCUUCUGGCAGCGUUCCUGCCCACAGGCCAGAGACUGGUGUAUUUCCUCCAGUUUGGAGCUUCUGGUAUGUUCUCGGUGACUGGUCAAGGCUGGGCUAUUUCAGGACUUGGAGAACCUCCUCGGCCUGUUAUUGCUCGGGAAGUUUCCAGAAGGCUGUAGAUGCGUAGCUGGCUGUCCAGUCCCAUUGCAUCUUCCCUCUUGAGCAAAUAGCUAAACGUGCGCUUCAUCCCUCCACUCAGGCUGUGCUAAUAGGAAACCAAAGCGGCCAAGGGGCUGGACAUGUGGAUGGAGGGCUCUGCCUCGCAGCACCUCCAAAACAGUUGCCACUUACAGAGAGCACACUAAGUGCAGACGCUGUGCUGUGUGCUCUGCAAAUGUCACUCCUCGGCCUCCCCUCUGCACCGAGACAACUGCUACCAUGAGAAUCCUGUCUUGAGGAAGCCCAGAGGGGCAAGGUGCCUGCCCAGGUCACAAGGUUGAUGAGCAAUUGGCCAAGUCACUGUUUUAUCACCACGGAAUCACUGCUGGAGUUUGGUAAUGGUCGUUGUAUGUGAAUGCCUCUGUGCUCCCCUACAAAAUGACUGAAGCAGACUCAGACCUCAACGGUGCAUUCUAGGGAUGCCUUCCAGUUACUGAAUGGCGUACUGGGGUUAUGUGCAUUGCCUUGCUUAAUUUUCACGAUAAGGCAGUAGAGCCACAGUUAAAAUUUGGCCUCAGCAAGUCCCGGGUUCGAAUGCGGCUUGUGCAGCUUUUGAGUUGAUUACCCUGUGUCUCUUGUUCAGCAUCUCAGAGCCUGUUUUUUCUUCAGGGCUGCUUUGAGAAUUCAGUGAAUGAAUGUAUGGGCAAGACUUAGGACAGUGCCCGGCUCAUAGUCAGCUCUCAAGAAAUAGGUCUCAGCAUAGUAAUAAUUAUCAUUAUAUUUAGAUAAUUAUGUAGUCCGUUUUACACAUGAGGGAAGUGGGGCUAAGAGCAGUUCAGGAACUUGUUCAAGAUCAGCCAACUAAUAAAUACCAGGGACACCCAGCUCCAUCUGUUGCCAAAGCUGUCGCAGCAUCACGCACUUCCCGCAGAACACCGUGCUGUGGCUGUUUAUCUUCUUGAAGUUCCUCAGGGAGUCAGUCUCUUUUGUUUCAGGAGCUCCCUGACACCGUGGUGAACUUGGCCGGUCAUCCAAACCCACUCCCGCGCCCAGCCCGGGGCCAUGACCCCUAAGAGGGGGAGAGCAGUGUUCAUUUUGCUCUUCACCAUCGUUUUGAGUGCUGUAAAUGGUAAUAAUCCUGAUGCCCAGGGCUCAGCUUCCAAGAACAAGGAUGCCCUCAGCUCCCUGUCCCUGCCUGCACCUCCGGCUGCUUCCUCUCCUGCAGGAGGAAGGGCAGGGAACAACUGCUUCACCACUGAUAACAGCAAGAGAGCAACACGAUGCGGCGGUCACGUCUUCCACCAAAAACAAGCUAGAGAAGCACAAUAGCUCAGCACUUCACUGGCUGCUGCCUCCCGUUCCCUGCUAUUUUCAUGAACCAAUUUUCUUUAUCUUCUGUCUUUGGCAAGGGCAGCAUUUUUGAAGAUGCAUGUUAAUGUUUAAAAUACCCAAUAGCUGGUGCACAAUUUUUCUGUUUCUUUUAAUUAUCUCGUUCACUUUUUCCUCUGUAUUCAUUGUAGAUCUUCUAUUCCUCUGCCCUCUCUAAAAAUGCGUUGCAUAUUUAUAUUGUUAUAAACCCUCCUGUGCUCUUCCAGUAACUGUUCUCAGCAUAACCAGAGAGGUGCCCUUUCCCCACUAAAAUUUUAACAGAGCACAGCUUUUAAUUACCUUUUCCCCAUCUCCGACAGGAAAAUUUCCGAACAUAAAAUAAUAAUCAAAAAACUUCCAAGUAUAACUUGCAACCCGAGAGCCAGACUCAACAAAGAUAAGUCCCCGUUUCUUUCUUCUGAAUAUCUAAAGUUUCCUGCAAGCCCCAGUGGUGCCUCUCACAUGUCCCAGGCCUCUGGCCAGGUUCCAGCCUCACUCACUGCUUGCUAGAUGUCCCACUGGAGCGUAUGCUCUCGGUGCCCAGCAAGAAAAGGUGCUCCCUUCUCUGAGCCAGGCCUCCCCGCAAGACCUUGGCACCUUCCGCCUGUUUUCCUGACUGCCUGUGGGUUGAGGUGGCAUAUGAGAACUACUUGACUGUCUUUUAAAACUCAUGUUGCUUCCUUUGACUUCCUAUCUGCUGUGUCGGCCAAAAUACUGUUAUUCAACAGAUUGCUAGAGGGUGGGAAUUGGCAUAGAGUUUGGUAUAAAGUCAAGGCUGGACACACAAAGGAGUCCCUGGCCAUGCAGGCACAGAGCACAUUCUUGUGGCUGUCACCCAGCUGUGCCACAUGAGGUCACAGUCCUUCGACCUGCUGUCUCCAUGCCUGUCCCCUCCCCAGGCUGCAGGCGCUGGGGUUGCCUUCCCUGUAAACUCCUCCUGUGACUGUCCCCAUCAGCAGCCCCACCAUCCCCUGCUUAGCUGGCUUGGCUCCUCAGAAGCACCUCUGCAGCCAGGGCCACAUCCUGCUGACUGCAUGGCCUUCAAGCCCCCCACAACCCCCGCCAUCCCUGUGCCUCCACCUCUAUCUCAGCUCCUUGGAUGCUCCCAGCGUCCACCAGACAACCCCAGCCUCCUCAGUUGGCCCUAGAGGCACCAAGGUGUGCCAUCCUCUGGCCUUUCUUUUUUUUUUUUUUUUUUGAGACCGAGUCUCGCUCUUGUCUCCUAGGCUGGAGUGCAGUGGCGUGAUCUUGUCACUGCAACCUCUGCCUUCUGGGUUCAAGCGAUUCUCCUGCCUCAGCCUCCCAAGUAGCUGGGAUUACAGGCGCUUGCCACCACGCUCAGCUAAUUCUCAUAUUUUUGGUAGAGAUGGGGUUUCACCAUGUUGGCCAGGCUGGUCUCGAACUCCUGACCUGAGGUGAUCCGUCCACCUUGGCCUCCCAAAGUGCUGGGAUUACAGGCAUGAGCCACCCUGCCUGGUCAUCCCACUGCCUUUCUUACCUCACCAGGCACCUCGACCCUUGGCCCAUCCACACUCUGGCCCGCACCUGCUUUUUGCUAGAUUUACCUGUUCCACACCUCUGACCACUCCCUUGGCCACAUCACUCACCAGCCCAGGCCUUUUCAUUAUCCCUAUAUCAGCCCAGCUCUUGAGGCCCGCCCCCUCCUGUGGAGUUACCUCCUGCCCUAUCAGCUAAUCAACAGCAAAGCUUCCCUGGUCCAUCAUAUCUAGUACCAUUGUUUCAAAACAACAUUGCAACUUUCUCCUUUUUAUUUUUCCCCUCUUAAAUUAAAAAGAAACUCACAAGUGAUGCAAUAAAUCAAAUAACAGAAAAGGGUAUAACAAAACUGAAGUACUGCCCUGUCUCCCUCUGACCCUGCCUGCCCUGAGACCUGGUAUCAACAGUCGAGGCCCUGUUUAUUUCUGUGCUUUCCUGGGACUGUCUGCAGGUGCUCCCAGGCCUCUGAGGAUCCACUUGUGUCUGAACAUCUCUACCCAGUGACAACUAUCUCCCCAGUCUCAGGUCACAAAAACAUCUUUGUGUGUACCUGGUGGAGUUAAAGUGUACGAUUGUGUUCAAUCCUUUAUUCCCAAAGCUGGUGAGUUUUUACCUCCCCUUCUGGUGCUGAAAAUAGUACGUAACCCAUCAGCGUGUGCAGCGCAGCAUGUGCAGGGUUCUGCAGAUUGAGGUUCUCAUGGGUUAUCAUGGCUAACUUUGCAAAUUGAGUCCCUUUCUAUCUGCUUCCCAUGGUACCUGACCCAGCGUUUGGUGUGUGCCCAACCAAUGCAAACUGAUCUUAAAUAUUGCCUGAGGCAAAGAGAAUUAAGACGGGAAAUCUGUUUGAAAGAAGUGGUGGGACAGCCACCUGUCUCCACAUGGCUUAAUCAAGAAGGUAACUGAAUAAAUGUGCACUUACGGGUCACAUGUACAGGUUUACUUCAUUUUCAUGAAAUGACUUGUAUCUCUGUUUAAUGUUGCUUUUUGCAAAUCAAAUUGUAUUCCCUUUGGCUCCUUAAAAUUUCAGAGACAAUUUUCCAUAACUUUUAAUUGACCUUUAACUGGCACUGAAUCUUAAUUUAAGCUUUCAAUUGCUUUUGCCAAGUUUUUAUACUAAUGUUCUACUAAACAGUUAAGGCCCCUAGAGGAGCCCCCAUCUUAAUCAUAACAAAAAAAUCUAUUACUUUACCAUUUGUAUAAUGUUUUAUAGUUUUCCUGUAUAGAGUGUAGUAUGAAUAAACGCCUUCAAAAUUCUCCUUUUUAAA